AUGGAAAGUAAAUGGUAGCUCGGAAGGGUCAAAAGAGUCCGCGGUUUCGCCGCGUGAGUUGCUUUUUGCGGCUGGGGAGGUCUACGCUUCUAGAGCUUGAGCCAGCGGGGCGACCCUGCAGUGGCAGGACUCGGCACCGCGCCCUCCACCGCCGGUUGGUGGCCUGCGUGACAGUUUCCUCCCGUCGACAUCGAAAGGAAGCCGGACGUGGGCGGGCAGAGAGCUUCAUCGCAGUAGGAAUGGCAGCCCCAUCUAUGAAGGAAAGACAGGUCUGCUGGGGGGCCCGGGAUGAGUACUGGAAGUGUUUAGAUGAGAACUUAGAGGAUGCUUCUCAAUGCAAGAAGUUAAGAAGCUCUUUCGAAUCAAGUUGUCCCCAACAGUGGAUAAAAUAUUUUGAUAAAAGAAGAGACUACUUAAAAUUCAAAGAAAAAUUUGAAGCAGGACAAUUUGAGCCUUCAGAAACAACUGCAAAAUCCUAGGCUGUUCAUAAAGAUUGAAAGUAUUCUUUCUGGACAUUGAAAAAGCUCCACUGACUAUGGAACAGUAAUAGUUUGAAUCAUAGUGAACAUCAAUACUUGUUCCCUAUAUACGACACUUGAUAAUUAAGAUGAUCAAGAACCAGAAGAUCUGUGAAGAAAUGAAAUAAAAUGGUAUUUAGUAAGAAAUCUCUAUUUUAAGAAAAAAAGUAAAACCUGUUAUAAACACAUGCACUUUUGUUUUGUUUUUGUUUUGUUUUUAAUUAGAGGAUGGGUAGUAGGCAGAUGAUAAAAUUUAUAAUAUACAUAGAAGUGAAAUAAAUGGGAGUUAGCAUUUUAAUACAGGCAAGAGCUAUUACAACAACCCAAGUGAGAAAUGAUGAGGGUUUGUGGAAGGUUUAUAAGGAAGAAGGGUGAACUUAAAAUAUACAAGUAAAAUAAUAAAAGCCAUCUAUAAAAAAGCCCAUAGCUAAUAUCAACACUUAAUGUUGGGACAGGAACUGGAUGUCUAGCUAGUCCAGUGAGACAAAAAAGAAAAAGCAUACACACUGGGAAGGAAGAAAGAAAACUAGCUCUACUCACAUAUAAUAAAUACUAUCUUAUAGAAUGUACCAAUGGAUGCACAAAAAGAGCUCCUAGAACUAUAAGUCAAUCAUAGAAAGGUUGCAGGAAACAAGGUCAAUAUACACAAGGAAAAUUAUAUUCCUAUAUAUCAGCAAUAAACAACUGGAAUUUAAAACUUAAAAAUACCAUUUGUGAAUAGCACCAAAAAAAAUUAAAGGAAUACUUAGGUAUAAAUCUAAUAUAUGGAGGCCUCUAUGCUGAGAACUAGAAAACACUUGGAAGCAGACUACAUCAGAUUAAAUGGAGAGGUAUACAGUUGGCCCUCUGUGGGUUCUGCAUCCAUGGAUUCAACCCCGAAGAGAAAAUUUUUGGGAAAAGGAAAAACGAGUAAAAAUAAUAAAAAUUUAAAAAUCCAGUAUAACACCUAUUUACAUUGUAUUAGGUAUUGUAAGUCAUUGAGAUGAUUUAAAGUAUAGGCAUACCUCAAAGAUACUGCAGGUUUGGUUACAGACCACUGCAUUAAAGUGAAUAUCACAAUAGAGUGGGUUACACAAAUGUUUUGGUUUUCCAGUACACAUAGAAGUUAUGUUUAUACUGUUGUCUAGUAAGUGUGCAAUAGCAUUAUGUCUGCUCAGUAUAUAUGCCUUCAUUUUAAAAUACUUUUUAUUACUAAAAAAUGCUAAAGAUUCUCUGAGUCUUCA